CCGGCCUCACGCGACCCACCAUUCCCGCCGCCCCCUCACGGUGCCCGCCGUUCCCGCCGCCCGGCUUUCUAACCGGGCCCCUAGUUCCCCGCCCCGUGCCCUCUGGAGACCUGCAGCUCCUGCCGCCCUGCGCCCGCUCCCAGGGCCCGUCGUUCCGCCGCCCUAUCCCUCCUCAAGGGGCCCCUAGCUGCCUCCUCGCGACCCUUUCCGGACUCGGCCUGCCCACUCCUGCCCGCUAACCCGCCUGGCUCCCGGGCGAGAGCCCUCGCGCGGCUCUGGUUCCUGUUCCUCUAACGCCGCCGGGGCUGCGGGAUGCCGACUCCGCGGACCGCCCAGACCCGGAACUGCUGAGGCAGCAGCGGGCUCGCGGCGCUUGGCUCAUCCCGGGAUUCCCCAGCUCUCGCGCUGGGCCCGCCGCGUUCGCACCAAGCACGCCAGGCGGCCCUGGCCUACCUCCCUCCCGCCUCCCGGCAGCUGGCACGAGGGAACCUGGCCGUCAGGUUUCCCCUGGGAUCCUGGGACGGUAUCAGGCGGGGAAUCUGUGCGGCCGCGGCGAGGCUCAGGACGAGGGACGGGGCGGCAAAUUGUCACAGAGGUCGCCGUAGACCGGUGUGCAACCGAAGGUGAAGAGCGGGAAGGCGAGGACCGAAUCGCCUCUGGUGUGCGUUGUCCGACAGGAAGUCCCGAAUGGGCUGUGAGCCGCCGGUGGAGGUGCCCGGGCAGGUGCAGAGCCACAGCCUGCGCCCCGUGAGCCGAGGCGGGUGAUUUAUUUGGCAUAAAAGUAUUCUUUCAAGGAUGGCAGAAGCUGUUUUGAUUGAUCUUUUUGGUUUGAAAUUGAACUCUCAAAAAAACUGCCAUCAGACAUUACUGAAGACUUUGAAUGCUGUCCAAUACCACCAUGCUGCCAAGGCCAAGUUUCUCUGUAUAAUGUGUUGCAGUAACAUCAGCUAUGAAAGGGAUGGAGAACAAGAUAAUUGUGAAAUAGAAACAAGCAAUGGAUUAUCAGCUCUCUUGGAAGAAUUUGAGAUUGUUAGCUGUCCCAGCAUGGCUGCCACUUUGUAUACCAUUAAACAGAAAAUUGAUGAAAAAAAUCUGAGCAGCAUUAAGGUAAUUGUACCCAGGCACAGGAAGACAUUAAUGAAAGCUUUUAUUGAUCAACUCUUCACUGAUGUUUACAAUUUUGAAUUUGAAGAUUUGCAAGUGACUUUUAGGGGAGGGCUUUUUAAACAGUCCAUUGAAAUAAACGUAAUCACAGCUCAAGAACUAAGAGGAAUUCAGAAUGAAAUAGAAACAUUUUUGAGAAGUCUGCCAGCACUGAGAGGAAAAUUAACUAUUAUCACUUCUUCUUUGAUCCCAGAUAUUUUCAUACAUGGAUUUACUACAAGAACAGGUGGGAUAUCUUAUAUACCAACUCUUAGCUCAUUCAAUCUCUUCAGUAGUUCCAAACGGAGAGAUCCCAAGGUAGUGGUUCAAGAAAAUCUGCGUAGGUUGGCGAAUGCUGCAGGAUUUAAUGUGGAGAAAUUUUACCGAAUAAAGACUCAUCAUUCCAAUGACAUCUGGAUUAUGGGAAGAAAGGAGCCUGACUCUUAUGAUGGAAUAACCACAAAUCAGAGAGGAGUCACAAUAGCAGCUCUUGGUGCAGACUGUAUACCGAUAGUUUUUGCAGAUCCAGUCAAAAAAGCAUGUGGGGUUGCUCACGCUGGUUGGAAAGGUACUUUGUUGGGUGUUGCUAUGGCUACAGUGAAUGCUAUGAUAGCAGAAUAUGGCUGCAGUUUGGAAGACAUUGUUGUUGUACUUGGACCUUCAGUAGGACCUUGCUGUUUUACUCUUCCAAGGGAAUCAGCAGAGGCAUUUCAUAAUCUUCAUCCUGCAUGUGUACAACUAUUUGAUUCACCAAAUCCCUGUAUCGACAUCCGUAAAGCCACAAGAUACUUGACUGGAUUUUUGUAUAACUGCUUCCUGCCUCCUUCCAAACUGACUGCAAGAGAGAAAUUUAGCUGUUUGAUUUACUUAAAACCAAAUGGAUUACAAUGGAUAAUUCAUCUUUUGGGUAUAUUUUUACUAUUAUUCAAAGCCAAAUGAUUUUCAUUUAAUUGUAAUAAUAACUGACAAAAAUCAGUAUGUUGUAGCUAAUAUGUUUUAUGCAUGAGAAUUAUUCUUAAAGUUUGUUCUCCCUGUUUAUUACACAGAUCAGGAAUAGAUUUGUUCAGUUCAGUAUUUAUUGGAUACCCUCUAUUGGUCAGGCAUUGUGUUAAGCAUAUGUGAAUCAAAAUGAACACAACUUUUUCCUUUGAGUCUGAUACAGUGAAGGAGAUAAACACUUCUACAACUUAAAUUUAAUUUUAAUAGCAGUAGAAGAGAACAUAAGGAAUAGAGGUUAAUUUUACCCAGAAGCAGGAUAGAGAAAAUAUUACAGAGAAAAUCACAUAUCACAUGGGCUCGAAAGAUGUAGAGGUUUUUGACAAAUGAAGAACAACCAUAACAGGUAGAGGGAACACCAUGAACCAGGGCAUGAAACUGAAAGUGCAUAACAUAUUCUAGAGAGAGAAGGGUGUGGGCAUGAGUUAGGGCUGGAAAAACAGGUUGGAAACAGAUAAGUAAGGGUCUCAAAUGCAAUGUCAAAGAGCUUGCAGUUUAUUUUCCAGGCAAUGAGUAGGCAGCCAAAAAAAAAAAAGUAAGGAUGUUUUUUUUUUUUUUCCCAUGGCAUCAUAUUUAAGAGGAUGGAUUUAAAUUGUGUGAGACCAAAGCAUAGAGACUAGAUAAGAGGCGAUCAAAAUAUUUCAAAAAGAAAUAAUGAAGAUCCAAUGAAGGAAGUGGAAAUUAAAAUAGGGAAGAGAGUAGAUGGAUUAGAGAGACAUUUAAGAGAUGGAAUCAAUAGAUCCUGUUACUAGAUAAUGGAAGUAAGAGGUGAGGAAGAGUGGAAAAGUCAUUAAUGACUCUAAGAUUUCUGCUUGGCUGCUUACCAAGAUUGGCAACAAAGGGAGGGAGAAGGUUUGGAAAAAGAGAGAAGGAUAAUGAGUUUGACUUUACAUAGAAUGAAGGGCAUCCAGAUAGAAAUCUUUGGUUAAUAAUUAGAAAUAUAGACCUAGAAAUUAGGAGGAAACCUGAGACAGAGACAAAUAUUUCAAAGCUUACAAUACAGAGAUGAUACCUGAUUCUAUUGGAGCAGGUUUGAUCAUCUAGGCAGAAAUUAGGAUGAGAAAAAAGGAGAUCCAAUAAUACAACCUUAUAGUCACAGAAGUAAGAAAAAAAGGGUAGUUGUUUUGAAGAAGCCAGGAUAGGUGUGGAAAGUACUCAAAAAGAAAUCUUCAGGGAUAAAAUAAAGUGAUAAUUUAAAAGAAAUCAAUGGAUUAAACAUAUUGAAACUGUUCUAUAGGCAGUGGUCAUUGAGUCAGCUUUCAGUGCAUUAGGAAGAAGAUGCAUAGGUGUCAACUCUUUUCUGACAGCAUUUACUAGAGAAGAGAAAAAGCUGGGGACUACAUCUUCAAGGAAGGGACUUUUUUUGGAUGAGCAGUUUUGAGUGUGUUUGUCAGUUAAAGAGAGGAAUUAGGUUAGUUUUCAUUUGGGAAAAAUUGUAUAUAUAUUUAAUGUAAGUUAUCACAUUGCAUCUUAAAAAUAUUCUUAUUUAAUACAUAUAUUUCCUACAUGUAUAUGUGGUAGCAUGAUAGCAAAUAACAUUUGUUUGGUAUUUCCAAAGGACUUUCAUGUACAUUGCCUCAUUUUACCUUUACAGCUACUCUGAAAUACACAGGCAUUAUCCCUUUUAUUCAGCUGAGAAAACUGAGCUUCAUUGAGGUGGAGGUCAAAAAUCACAAAAUUUGUGAUGAAUUAAGAUUUGAACAUAUGUUUUGUGACUCCAGUUUUCCUUUCAGAUUUUAAAAUUAAUUAAAGGGAUCUUCAUUAUACUUUUAUUGUUAACUUUUUGUUAACAUAAUUUAUUCAUACAUUCAGUGAAAAUUUUGUUGAGGUACUGGGACAGGUUAAAAAAUACAGUUGUAGCCCUCAGGAUAUUUAAUAUCCAGUGAAAAGUGACAGUCAGUAAACCAACAAUCUCAAUACUUUGAUAUAUGUUGUGAGGUUGUGAUAACCGAUUCUUGUUUAGUUUAAUUCUAUAUCUCCCUUAGACCAGUGUUAAAUUUAAAUAAAACACCUCAUUUUUUCCAAUUCAGGGAAGGCACUAAACAUAAAGCAUAGGAUAGAAAUGUUGAACUCAUCCAAAAUAUUAUUUUGUUUAAUGAAAAUGAUGAAGAUUAAGGAAUACUUCCAUGUAUUGAGUAAGGUUGAUAAUUUUCUAAUUCUUCACUGUGCAUUAUUUUGUUUGAAGUUGGUAAAUUUGGAGUAUCCUGCAGACACAUUUUGCUUUAUGUACUACAACAUUCUACAACCAAAUAAAAAUUAUUUUGAUUAUCUGA